GGCGACGACCAGAAGGGGCCCAAGAGAGGGGGCGAGCGACCGAGCGCCGCGACGCGGAAGUGAGGUGCGUGCGGGCUGCAGCGCAGACCCCGGCCCGGCCCCUCCGAGAGCGUCCUGGGCGCUCCCUCACGCCUUGCCUUCAAGCCUUCUGCCUUUCCACCCUCGUGAGCGGAGAACUGGGAGUGGCCAUUCGACGACAGGUUAGCGGGUUUGCCUCCCACUCCCCCAGCCUCGCGUCGCCGGCUCACAGCGGCCUCCUCUGGGGACAGUCCCCCCCGGGUGCCGCCUCCGCCCUUCCUGUGCGCUCCUUUUCCUUCUUCUUUCCUAUUAAAUAUUAUUUGGGAAUUGUUUAAAUUUUUUUUUUAAAAAAAGAGAGAGGCGGGGAGGAGUCGGAGUUGUGGAGAAGCAGAGGGACUCAGUGUGGUGUAAAGGAAUUCAUUAGCCAUGGAUGUAUUCAUGAAAGGACUUUCAAAGGCCAAGGAGGGAGUUGUGGCUGCUGCUGAGAAAACCAAACAGGGUGUGGCAGAAGCAGCAGGAAAGACAAAAGAGGGUGUUCUCUAUGUAGGCUCCAAAACCAAGGAGGGAGUGGUGCAUGGUGUGGCAACAGUGGCUGAGAAGACCAAAGAGCAAGUGACAAAUGUUGGAGGAGCAGUGGUGACGGGUGUGACAGCAGUAGCCCAGAAGACAGUGGAGGGAGCAGGGAGCAUUGCAGCAGCCACUGGCUUUGUCAAAAAGGACCAGUUGGGCAAGAAGCAUCCAAAAUACAAACCAUCUAAGAGGCAAGAAAAUGUCGUGAUGUUCCUAGUGCAAGUUAAAAAGAUUUGCUUUCCUCAAGUCGGAAAGCCCUUCUCAUUUUUGAGGUUUUUUUCUUCUUUUUUUUUUCAAGUGAAAGCAUUUUGGAGGAGUCAAUAUCCAUCUUUAAAGGUAGCCAGGUCACAUGUAUACAUAUGUAACUAACCUGCACAAUGUGCACAUGUACCCUAAAACUUAAAGUAUAAUUUAAAAAAAAAGAAUUUAAAUAAAAAAAGAAAAUCAGAGAGAAAAAAAAAAAGAUGCAUGUGCACCCUGAUACUACCAUCCAUAGUGAUACGGUUUGGCUUUGUGUCCCCACCCAAAUCUCAUCUUGAAUUGUAACCCCCAUGUGUUGAGGGAGGGACCUUAUGGGAGGUGAUUGGAUCAUGGGGGUAGUUUCUCCAUGCUGUUCUCAUGAUAGUGAAUGAGUUCUCAUAAGAUCUAAUGGUUUAAAAUCAUGGCACUUCCUUUUGCUCUCUCUUUCUCCUGCCAUGUGAGGUGUGCCUUGCUUCCCCUUCCCCUUCUGCUAUGAUUGUAAGUUUCCUGAGGCCUCCUCAGCUAUGCAGAACGGUGAGUCAAUUAAACUUCUUUCUUUAUAAAAAAAAAAAAAAAAAAAAAGGUAGCCAGGUAAAAAUUACUUGUUUCCAGGACAUUUUCACCUGAAAGAAGCAUUGUCAUAUAACAUAGAAGCAAGAAAUCCAGUAGUGGGGGUUAUUUAAAAAUAGCUGGAAAAUUUCAAUCAGCAUGAGUUUGAAGCAACAAUUUAUCAUCACCUUUUAUGGUGGGUGGGGUUAAGAACAUUUCAGCGGGCAAAGUGGUGGUGAUGGGGAAGAGACACCAGGGGAGGUGAUUCCCAUUGCAUUGCUUUGUAAACAGAGGCACAGGUUCUUCAUUUUUGUCACACAAAAUCACAGCUAUGCAGAAUUUAUUAAUUUAUUCUUCUGAGACAAGAAAAAAGCCACCAAAGGAAACCAACAGCUUGCUCCUCUCACACUGGGGGAACCAUAUGAGAGACUUAUCUAUCCCUGACUUUAAUUUUGACCUGAGGAGAGCUCCUCUUAAGGAAAACAAAUUAAUUCAAUGACUAUACUACUUAAUCAUUGACCUUUAUUUAAUAAGAGAUUUUUCCAUAGGAUAUGCUGAGCUGUCUCACUUACAUCAGUUGUGUCUCCUGAGGUGGGUGACAGGAGACCACAAAUAUUGCAUAGCACACAAAUCGUUAAUAGCAGCUGUAUACCAAACCAUUACCUAAAUAUGUAGAGUACAAUUCAUUCUCACUAAUGUCAGAGAGCAUGCUAUAAAAUGGUGAAUCCGGACAGCUGAAGAUACUGAAUAAUAACCUCUAUUUUGAACAAGUUUACAGUGUUCCAAUCAGUAAUUAAAUUGAUACCUGAUGAAUAUAUGUGUGUGUAUGUAUUCAUAGCAGAGAUGGUUUUCCUGAGAUAAGGAUUUUGUUAUUCGGAUAGGCUGCUGCUGGAAUUGUCCUUCUACCCUUGUUUCUUUGUCCUUAGUCAUCACUCAUACCUCUUUCCACUCUUCUGCCAUCACUUUUGUCACCAAAGUCAUGGUCCUUUCCCCGCCGAUUGCUGCUGCAGGUCUAGGGCACCAAGACUUAGGCAGCACUCACCAUGUGCCAAGAACUGGACCACAGGUACCAUCCAGCAUUGCUCAUGGAGACUCUGUCCCUUUCUGUAGGACACCCUCCUUUUAGCUAGCAACCCCUCCACCACCUAGAGCCUCUGGACCUCUCAUUUUAAUAUUAAGAACUAGGAAAACUUACCGCUGAGAAUAACUAGUACAACUAGAACUGGUAGAGAAAUCUGGGUCUCUUGGGAAUGGAUUUUUAGGCUUUAUUGAUUAGAGGUGUAUUAAUAAUGCAGUGUUAUAGUUUCAUGACAUAACGAAUAAAAAAGUUCAUUUUGGACUUGCCUUUCAGCUCCCUAGGAGCUAAAAGACGUAUUUAAUGUAACUUGUGUGGUGGAAAUAAGUUCUUUUUUCAGGCAAAAGAUGUGCAAACCCAUCUGGGGAAGAAACAUUAAAAACUAAGGAGACAGUGUCCUAGAUAACUAUGUUCUUUUCCUGUUUUAGUCUAAAAUAAUGAUUAGUUUUCUUAUAUAUCUUCAUUUGUCUUGGUUCCUUUUAGCCCAAUUUAAUAAUAUUAUUGCAGAUAUUGAUGAAAACCUUUACCUUCCUCUUAAUUCAUCAAAGUACUUGAUAAAAUUUAUACAUAGUACAUUAAUUGGGAGGUUUUUAUGAGAUUAAUUAAUAUAAUGAACUGAUGUUGAAAUUAUUUAAAACCUGAAUUAUUAUUGUAUUAAGUAGGACACUUAAUACAGUUAAUCAGUUCUGUCUUUAUUCAUUUGUGAGAAUUUUUGGCAAGCUAUUGUGAAUAUUCAGGGAAGGGAAUGUAUUUUUAGCAGGAAUCUUAUACCUCCUACAUAGAAAUGAAGCAUUUACUGAAACAUCCAUGAAACAAAAUGUUUCUGAAUGUGUACUAUACACUUGUUAUAAGCCCCUUUUCUUCUGUAGCUAUAUUUUGGAGAAAAAUCUUUGCUUUGACAAAAAAAAUUAUGUUGACUUACACAUAUAUUUUAUAACUAAGCAGUGUUUGGUUUGUGAUAAAGGAUACAAAAAUAUAAAAAUGUUCAGCACACGUAAGUAAGGCCUUGUUGACAGUGUGAGUUAUGCUACUGGAUACUCAAAAGGAACAUUCAGUGUUCUCAGGUGGUCUCUAGACUGUCUCAAGCCUAGGAAGAUAUUUUAUAAGCAAAGGAAUAAGAGAAGGAAGAUUCAGAUUUAAUCCAAGUGAAGAAUUCAGUUUUGUGUGCCUUAUCCUGUUAUUUUGAGAGGCAGCCAAAAGAUGCUGGUCAGCAAGGAGAAUUGUAAGUUGGGCAGCCAACUCUGAUUUCUCAACCUCUUAGCUGUUUUCUUAAACUCAGAAUUUUUAAUGAAUUUAAAUGUCCAUAUCAGGUAGACUUUGGGGAUGCUUUUACCAGUGAUUUUCAGAAUGUUACUUUCUGGCAUUUCUUUUCACGUAGCAUUAUAUUAAAAAUGAAUUCAUUCAUCCACCUUCCCUUGUCCUUACUAAUUUUCCCUCCUACUCCCUUCCCCCUUGUUCUUGCCAUGGGGACAUGCAAACACUGGUGGUUGAUGUCUGAGCAAGGCUGCUGACAGGGGGAGGAAGGAGAUGUCAAGCAGAGGUCAAUGGCAGUGUGCCCAGCAGCCUAGGAAGUAGGAGGGAAAAGAGAGAGAGACAGAGAUGGUGGAUGAAAGAGAAAGCCAGGAUGAUUAUGGUGGUUAUGAUACUUGUCAUGCUGAACACCCAAUUGAGCACCCAAUAAGCACAUAAUAAUUUAAUCAUCCUCUGGCUUGGAUGGCAGUGUUCUAUCAGUGUUGACUUCCUGGUUGUGACAGUUUUACAGUGUUAGUGUAGAAGAGAAUCCUUGCUUUAGAGAGGUACUUACUGAAGUACUUAGGGUUAAUGCACCAUUGUGCUGGAAAAAGAUACGCACACACACGCACACACACACACACACACACUCUCACACACACGCACAAAUACAUCCAUGUGUUAGGCAGAGGGAGCAAAUGAGGUAAAAUGUUAACAAUUAGGAAUUCUGGGUGAAGUGGAUAGAGGGACUCUUUGACUGUUCUUGAAACUUCUCUAUACAUUUGAUCUGUUUCAAAUUCUUCAGAAAAUCAAACUACAAAAACUUAAUUCAUUUAGUGAACAUCUACUGAACAUCUGUAUAUUAAAUAGUGUUAAAUGAAUGUCAAUUAAAAUGCUCAAACACAGUAGAGGUUGAUUCUCAUUCACAUAAGUCCAUGGUAGGUGUUUUUGGCAGGUGGGUGAGUUUCUCCCUUAGGGAGAUUGAGGAACCCAGACUCCUCCCAAGUUGCAGCCCCACCGUCUUCUGAGGGGAUGCAUCCAUACCCACUUCGAAGUAGCAUACAUUAUUUCCUUUCUCAUUCCUUUGGAUACCAGCCACAAUUUAUUCAAGGUAGACAGAAAAUUGUAGUAUAUAGCCAUAUGCCCUGACAAAGAAGGGAGAACAGAUUUUGGUGGACAACUAGCAAACUCUGAUACAAUCUGUUAUUAAGCACUGUGUGUGGAUAGAUGCUAACUAGAAGGAGAUUAUCUUCCCUUCAGCAAAUAUAAACUGAAUGCCGUUUAUUUGGUUGAAACUAAGCUAGAUCAUGGGAGUAUAGAAAUUUUAUAAGAAGACAUAGUCACUUCUGUCAGUGAGCUCAAGAAGAAUUAGUAUGCGGAAUGUAAUCAUACCUACAGGGGGCUUGUGCCACUUAAGUAAAAUGAAACAUUAUUUUGAGUACAAUUUAGCAAUAAAUGUACUACGAGAUCAUUAAAAAUCAUGUUUGAAUGUUAUUGUGUCAAGGAUGGGAAAAAGACUUUUGGGUUGUAGACUUGAUAAUUAUAGUUAAAAACAGUUUUUAUUCUUGUUUAGUCUUAUUUUUUAUGUUUAAACAUAUUUAUACUUGCUAACAUUUAUACUUGCUAAGUAAAGACUGUUUUUACAACCAUGACAAGAACAAAACAUAUUAGUAAUGCAAAUGCCACAUUUCCUACAAUCAACUAAUCACACUAACAUAUUUGCAUGGAAGAAUCACUGGGAUUGAUCUGGCCACGUGUGUAGUCAUGCCCAAAAUGUGAAGUCCAUCUGUUUUGCAAUUUUUUUUAACCACUGUUAUCCAAAUGCUCCUUGGAUUUUUUUUAUUAGUGGAUAUAUUUUGGAGGUCAGACACCCUCUUGGCUAGAUCAUCACCUUUAUAACAAAUAUAUAUACUAUUCUCAUGGAAAUAUAUUUAGACAUUGCCCUACUGGGAAUUUUUUUCAAGUAAUUAAUGUACAGCUUGUGCAACAGCUUGAUCUUGGCUUCAUGGAAAUAAUUCACUCUUAGCAGCAUCUAAUGCCACAAAGCAUUUAUGGAUGUCAGCUCAGAACUUACUUUUAUUUAUCUCUGAGUUACUUUUUUUUUUUUUUUUUUGAGACAGAGUCUCACUCUGUCUUUGGCUUGUCCCUAACCUCUUAACAGACUUAAUAUUAAGCUCCAUUUCACUCAGUCGUUCUGUUGUCAUAUAAAUGAGACAUUCUACAAGCAUAGUUUUUAGUUUCUGCCAGAGCAUCAUACAACAUUGUGAGCUAUGAUGAAGAUAAAGACCUAGAGAAGAUAUUUAAUAUGAAGUUCAUUAUCUAAUAUUUGGUAUGUGUGGCAAAAUAGCAAUCUACUGCUUGGUUCUGCUGUAAUCUAUUUACCCACCCAUCCCAUCUUUCUUUCAAUUUAAAAGGAUAAUGAUUUUAGUCACGAUUAUACAUAAACCCAUUACCAUAGGCAAUAAACAAUGGGGCAAACCAUUGGUCCCAUAGUUGGAGUGUGGUCUGAAGUGUGUUUUGGUGGAGAGAGAUCUAUGUCUGGAGAUAGCUAACAUGGAUUUGGAUCCCAGAUCUGCUCCUACCUGUUGCUGUGCCUGUGACCAAAUCAUGUGAUCUCUCUGGUUUCAGUUUACUUGUGAAUAAAGUAAAUACCUUCAUCAACACCUGUUUUUGAAUACAAUGUUUUUCUGUAAUUUUUGCUUCUUAUAAUGUUAUAAUGAUCAUCCUUACAUCUAAAUCUUGGUUUACAUUUUCAUCAAUUCUUUUGGAAAGAUUGGAGAAGUAAAUUUUGGAGAUGUAUGUCGGCUAUUAAAAAUGUUUAAUUUUUUAAUUAAAAAUUAAAAC